AGAGUUGGAGCGCGCGCGACCCCGGACUCCACGGAGGCCGCGGCGAGCAGGCGGAGCUGCGGGUCGGGACGCUCUGCGUGGGGCGGGGCGCAAGGGAGGUUUCGAGCCCGGAAGGUCCGGCGCCCAGAGCUAACGGGAGUCCCAGGUUAAACACUUUAAGAUGAGAAAAAUUGAUCUCUGUCUGAGCUCUGAAGGGUCCGAAGUGAUUUUAGCUACAUCAAGUGAUGAAAAACACCCACCUGAAAAUAUCAUUGAUGGGAAUCCAGAAACGUUUUGGACCACCACAGGAAUGUUUCCCCAGGAAUUCAUUAUUUGUUUCCACAAACAUGUAAGGAUUGAAAGGCUUGUAAUCCAAAGUUACUUUGUACAGACCUUGAAGAUUGAAAAAAGCACGUCUAAAGAGCCAGUUGAUUUUGAGCAAUGGAUUGAAAAAGAUUUGGUACACACAGAGGGGCAGCUUCAAAAUGAAGAAAUUGUGGCCGGAGUGGGAUGGCGCUAUCUUGGCUCACUGCAACCUCCGUCUCCCGGGUUCAAGCGAUUCUCCUGCCUCAGCCUCCCUAGGAGCUGGGAUUACAGGCACCUGCCACCACACCCAGCUAAUUUUUUUGCAUUUUUAGUAAAGAUGGGGUUUUGCCAUGUUGGCCAGGCUGGUCUCGAACUCCAGACCUCAGGUGAUCUGCCCACCUCAGCCUCCCAAAGUGCUGGGAUUACAGGUGUGAGCCACUGCGCCCGGCCCGGAAAAGCAAAUUUUAAAUGGAGAAGAGUAGGAAAGGCAUUUCAAAAGCCACCUUGGUAUACCAGAUAAGAGAUGUGAAGCAGAUAACAAGCCCCACUAAUGAAGACUCAUAAUCAGAAAAGACCCAGAAGGGGACUGCUCUGGGUCAGGUUCUCUAGAAGCAGAGCCUCCAACAAGGAUUCUUUGAAGAGUGAUUUAUUGAGGGAGCGCUCUCAGGAGAAACCUCUAAGGAAGUGAGAGAAGCAGGAUCAGGCAGAGGGAAAAAUUAAACAUGGCUUCUGCUGAAGUCUAGCCUCAGUCUGAUCCCAUAGGGAGCUCUGAAGCAUGACUGGCACCGGAGAAGUAGACUGCCCCACCUUGCAGCAAGGGAAAAGGCUUUGGAAUUUCAAAUCCAUCAGUCACUGGCUGUGGGCCACACUCAGGUGAAGGACAUAAUUUCACAGGUAUUUCUGGGUAAGAUAGCUCCUGUCAUGAGGGCAAAUUCUCAGGAAAGAGUGCAUCUGUGAGCCAUUAGCAGCCAACACUCACAGCAGCUGGCUCAUGAGUACAAUGGCUUGGUAAAAGGCAUCUGGGCAGAGCACCAACAACACCUACUAUAGCAGCGGUUCUCAAAGUGUGGUUCCUGGGACAGCAGGAUCAGCCUCACCUGAGAACUUGUUAGUAAUGCAAAUUCCCUAGCUCAACCUCAGAUCUGUCGAAUCGUAAACUCUGGAGAUGAGAACCAAGAAUCUGUGUUGCAGCAAGCCCUCCAGGUGAUUUUGUUGCAUGCCCAAGUUUGAGAACCAUUGAACUACACUGGCCUAUGGCUAGCAACUGUAAAACAAAAGGAUUGGAAUUGAACCCAAACCUCUUGCAGUCUCCUGCACAUAGCCCUUUUCCCACCUUUGCCCUUGUAGUUCUCCUCACUUGAAAUGCCCUUCUCCCUUCCCAUCUUCUCCAGGCUCCCAUCCCAAAUUAUGGAAGUACUGGGCAUCUUUGAAGACCAGCUCAAAUGCCACCAGCUCCAAAAAGCAUUGUUGGAUUCACCCAGCUCAGAGGAUUGCUGUCUCCUCUGUGCCCUCUGAGCACUUAGUCUUCACUCUAACAUAUACUCCACCUUGAGUUAUGGUCAUUGGAGUGUAUGUCUGGUCCCCUGUGAGAUUAAGCUGCUGGAGGACAACAGCUCUUCCUCGUCCAUCUUUGCAUAACUCUGCACCCAGAAAAGAAUCAAUGCUCAAUGUUUGAUGCAUUAAGUUGAAGAGAAUCUAAUUGGAAAGCCGGGGGUCUAUUUUUGUCAUUCUGAAAAGCUCCUCAGUUCCAGCUACUAUUAUUUAGUGAAAAUGGGGAGAUUUCUGUGCAUUUGUAGACACGAAUUGGAAGACCAUCAGAGAAGUGAUUCAGAAGAGGCUUGCCUUACAUCCUGUCUCCUUUUGUGCAACUUAGUACUUAGGAGGAACAGUGAGUGCUCAUCUGUGCUUCAGUCCCAUCAUUGUCACAGCUUCUCAUUUUCAGUAUAGCCUCACAAACUCAUGCCUAUGUUGGUCAUGAGUGGCUUUGGUAGGAUGGGGAAUUUUUAUUCAGCAUCCAUAUUGUCUUGUCCUCCUUCCACCUCCAACCCCCCAAAAAAGGGCCCGAGGAAGCAGUUGUGGGACAAUAAUUAUGAUAAUCGUAAUAAUAGCCAACACUUCAUGACACUUUCUCCAAGUCAGGCACAGUUCUGAGUGCUCUACUCAUGAAUCUAUGGACUAGGCACUAUUGAUACCCUGUUUUAUAGGUCAAGAUACCAAGGCAGCUUGAUCAAAGUCACCCAGCUGGCAGGAACAGAGCUAGGACUCUGGCCUUGAAGUUAGAGAUCCGGUUUGAAUCUCGGCUUGUUACUUACUAGUUCUGAGAAGUUAUGCAAGUUACUUAACUCUCUGAGCCUUGAUUUCCUCAUCUGUAAAAUGGGGAUAAUCAUCUCCUCUUUGAGAUAUAUAGAGAUUAAAUGAGAUAACAUAUCUGAAA